GACUGCCGGUCCACACAGCCCAGCACAGGGACCUUGUAGCAGGAGUGACAGCGAAUGUCAGCUGGGAAGACACAAGUCAGGCUGAGGUGAUGGGGUCUCUGACUUACCUGGGGAUAAGCUGAGCUGGGGGCAGGGGUGGAGGGUGGAGAAGAGCCCAUCCCGUAGGUGCUCCAACCUGUUUGGCUGUUUGGUCUAGCAAGCACAGAGCAGGUGAGUGAUGCAGGGAAAAUGGAAAGUGGGCGGCAGGUAAGGGUAGAGCUGUUGCUUUGUGAAAGGCCCACGCCCUACAUAUCUUCCAUCACUCCACCCCGUUUGGAGGUGAGUCAAGAGGGACAGAACUAUGAAGAAAAACAUGGGGCUGGAGAUAGAUGGAAUGUGAGGAAGAUACCAUGGGGAAAGAAUGUGGAUGGUGAAGGAGGAGAUGGAAACUUGAAAGAAGGAGAAAUAAUAAAAAUGAAAAUCAUGAGGGUUACAACACUGUCAGAAAUGCCUUGGAACUUGAGGCUGGCGAGAAAGCCAUCUGUGGCCAGCUUUAGCAAUUUACAAUUUACUCUUCACCUCCUGGAGCUGGCAAGAGUGUGGCAAGAGGAACCAGACCUGAAUAGAAUCCUCUCACCCCAGUAGCUCUUCAGCAGAAAGGAAUGAUACCUGAGAGACAGAUCACCAGAUUCCAUCUUAGCACCUUAUCAAAAUGGAGAGGGUGGAUACAGAAGGUGGCACCCCAAGUUUCCUGCUUCAGUUAAUUCAAGGUUUGGGCAGGCAAGAUUUGGUGACGCAGGGUCCGAGGGUGGAAGAGCCUGCUUCUCUGGACGGCCGCCCUGGGGACCGGGUGAAUCUCUCCUGCGGAGGAGUCUCUCAUCCCAUCCGCUGGGUCUGGGCACCCAGCUUCCCGGCCUGCAAGGGCCUGUCCAAAGGACGCCGACCGAUCCUGUGGGCCUCUUCGAGCGGGACCCCCACCGUGCCUCCCCUCCAGCCUUUCGUCGGCCGCCUACGCUCCCUGGACUCUGGUAUCCGGCGGCUGGAGCUCCUCUUGAGCGCGGGGGACUCGGGCACUUUUUUCUGCAAGGGCCGCCACGAGGACGAGAGCCGUACAGUGCUUCACGUGCUGGGGGACAGGACCUAUUGCAAGGCCCCCGGGCCUACCCAUGGCGCCUGCCCCCGCAACCGAUUCGACCACUCCCUAGAUUUGGUGAGACUAAUUCCACCCCAUUUUCUUUCUCCUACAUGCCCACUCCCCACCCCUCAAUUCCUGAGUCUGAGCCCUUGCUGGGAGCAGACACGUUGGUCACCUUCUCUCCAUCCUUCAGCUCUGUCCCCCCCACAUAGCUCCACUUGUGAAAACCGAGCCCCAGAGGCCAGUAAAGGAGGAAGAGCCCAAGAUUCCAGGGGACCUGGACCAGGAACCGAGCCUGCUCUAUGCGGAUCUGGACCAUCUAGCCCUCAGCAGGCCCCGCCGGCUGUCCACAGCGGACCCUGCUGAUGCCUCCACCAUCUAUGCAGUUGUAGUUUGAAGGGAAGCCCUUACUCCAAACCUCCCAAGCUAGGGGAUCCCAGCUCCCCAUAAUCCCUCUCCCCUCCUUGGUUCCUCACCUGGAAGAGGAAGGCACCAUGGUAUAGAAAUAAGUGCUAGACUGGGAGUUGGGAGACCUGGGUUCCAGGCUGUCUCUGCCACUGGUCUUACUUCUAAACUUACUCCCAUCUCUCCUAUAACCUCCAUGUCUCCCUCACCACCAGUGUCCUCUCUAUACCCAAUCAAGCCCUAGCUCCUUUUUUUUUUUUUUUUGAGACGGAGUCUCGCUCUGUUGCCCAGGCUGGAGUGCAGUGACACCAUCUCCCUCACUGCAAGCUCCGCCUGCCGGGUUCACACCAUUCUCCUGCCUCAGGCUCCUGAGUAGCUGGGACUACAGGCGCCCGCCACCACGCCCAGCUAAUUUUUUGUAUUUUUAGUAGAGACGGGGUUUCACUGUGUUAGCCAGGAUGGUCUUGAUCUGCUAACCUCGUGAUCCACCCGCCCCGGCCUCCCAAAGUGCUAGGAUUACAGGUGUGAGCCACCGCGCCCGGCCUGAUUCUUUAAGCUGUUUUUCUUUGUUGCUGGUGUUUUCUUUUUGGACUCCUCUUCCUUGCUCCAUAUCCCUACAGUAUUUCCCACCAUUCUAGGUUUGUCCCUUUCUCUUCUUCUGGGACACUCUCAUCAACAGUCAGUCCUCAGCCCCCUCCUCUGCAAAUGACACUCAGAACUCUCUCUGGCUCAGAUCUCAGAUUUGGGAUUAACAAACUUCCACUUAGACAUUCUGCCUGACUGACCUCAGGCAUUUCGCACUCUGAAUGUCAAACCCAACUCAUUGUCAUCUCUGAAGCUGCUCACUUAAUUCUCCUCUGUAUUCUCUUUAACAACCCAGUUGCCCAACCCAGAAACUGGGAGUCACGCAGACCUCCUUUCUCUCUUACUCCCACACAAUGAGCCAUGAAGUCCAGUCUUUCUAUCUUAACAUCACUGUCAAACCCACACUGUAUUCCAUGCCCAGCGCUGCCACGUGAAUGUACUCUGCUCACUUCCUUCCUGGAUUACCCAUAGCCCCACCUCAUCCUCCUACCCUUGCUUUCCUCCCUGAAGUCAGAGAGAUCCUACUCAAGAGAUAACUGCUCCUGACAGCCCUUAUUACAGAACUGAAGUACUCUCCUUAGCUUCAGCUCUGUGCCCACGUGCCUUGGCUUUGGAUACAAGGUACUACAGCACUUUGUCCACUCUCCAGGCUUACCUGUGUCAUUCCACAUGCACAUCUUAGAAAAUGCCAGCCUUAGAGAAUUCUCCCUAGCCCCAAAAUGUCUUUGCCCAGUGCAAUUCCUUCUUCCUGUAUUACCCCUUUCCCUCCUUCACACUAUCUGCCUGGCUAAUUCUUAUUUAUCCUUAGUUCAAGUAUGGCCUUUUCUGGGAAGGUGACCCUCCUUGGCCACCCCUUGCAUAUACUUUGAUGCCCUAGGGCACACCCCCUUUAUUUCCCUCAUAGAAACAGCCUUCUGUAAAUUGUUCCAUGACAACCUGUAUUUCAAUUUGUAAGAAAUUUGCAUGUACUGUGAGCUCCCCAACGUCAGGAGACUGACCCUUUUGAUAUCAUUGCUAAGCCUCAUUAAAUGAAUGAAUGAAAAUGAA